AGUCUGUCUCCGGCGCCGCCCGUCGCGGACUCGUCCUUGCUGCAGUCGCCGCCGCAGUCCUCGCCGCAGUCGCCGCCGCCGCCGCCGCCGCCGCCGCUGCUCCUCCGCCUGGCCUGGGCCGUCUGCCCGCAGCCAUGAGCGUGCUCGGCCCCGGUGGAGCCCGCAGUCCUCUAGAUUAGUCUCCACCGCCGUCCAGGACCCACUUGCAGCAUGGAGUCGCCCGCCUCGAGCCAGCCCGCCAGCAUGCCCCAGUCCAAAGGUAGGCGCUCCCGGCCGGGACCUCGGCCUGACCCCGCGCCUAAUCUGGGGCCGGGCUGCAAACCCCGACCUUUCUUUGGUCCCACCCCAUCCUGUUCUCGACCUGGCAGCGGCGUCCGGUCCCGGAACCCCUUCCUGUUCGGGGUCCCGGGACCAGCCCCCGCCUGGGCCCUCACCUGGACCCCCACGUUAGGCCUUGGGACUGCACUCAGGCCCGAGAUCACCCAGGCUGGACCCAGACUAGGACUUUGUUCUGCUCACCCCAUCCAAGUCAGGAGCCUCAUUCUGACCUCAUUUGGGCCUUAUGGCUGCAGCCUGGACAUGAACUCUCCCAGUCUUCUCCCUCAGCGGGACCCAGGAAAAUCCAAGAGGAAGAAGGAUCUACGGAUAUCCUGCAUGUCCAAGCCACCCGCACCCAACCCCACACCCCCCCGGAACCUGGACUCCCGGACCUUCAUCACCAUUGGAGACAGAAACUUUGAGGUGGAGGCUGAUGACUUGGUGACCAUCUCAGAACUGGGCCGUGGAGCCUAUGGGGUGGUAGAGAAGGUGCGGCACGCCCAGAGCGGCACCAUCAUGGCCGUGAAGCGGAUCCGGGCCACCGUGAACUCACAGGAGCAGAAGCGGCUGCUCAUGGACCUGGACAUCAACAUGCGCACGGUCGACUGUUUCUACACUGUCACCUUCUACGGGGCACUAUUCAGAGAGGGAGACGUGUGGAUCUGCAUGGAGCUCAUGGACACAUCCUUGGACAAGUUCUACCGGAAGGUGCUGGAUAAAAACAUGACAAUUCCAGAGGACAUCCUUGGGGAGAUUGCUGUGUCUAUCGUGCGGGCCCUGGAGCAUCUGCACAGCAAGCUGUCGGUGAUCCACAGAGAUGUGAAGCCCUCCAAUGUCCUUAUCAACAAGGAGGGCCAUGUGAAGAUGUGUGACUUUGGCAUCAGUGGCUACUUGGUGGACUCUGUGGCCAAGACGAUGGAUGCCGGCUGCAAGCCCUACAUGGCCCCUGAGAGGAUCAACCCAGAGCUGAACCAGAAGGGCUACAAUGUCAAGUCCGACGUCUGGAGCCUGGGCAUCACCAUGAUUGAGAUGGCCAUCCUGCGGUUCCCUUACGAGUCCUGGGGGACCCCGUUCCAGCAGCUGAAGCAGGUGGUGGAGGAGCCGUCCCCCCAGCUCCCAGCCGACCGUUUCUCCCCCGAGUUUGUGGACUUCACUGCUCAGUGCCUGAGGAAGAACCCCGCAGAGCGUAUGAGCUACCUGGAGCUGAUGGAGCACCCCUUCUUCACCUUGCACAAAACCAAGAAGACGGACAUUGCUGCCUUCGUGAAGGAGAUCCUGGGAGAAGACUCAUAGGGGCUGGGCCUCGGACCCCACUCCGGCCCUCCAGAGCCCCACAGCCCCAUCUGCGGGGGCAGUGCUCACCCACACCAUAAGCUACUGCCAUCCUGGCCCAGGGCAUCUGGGAGGAACCGAGGGGGCUGCUCCCACCUGGCUCUGUGGCGAGCCAUUUGUCCCAAGUGCCAAAGAAGCAGACCAUUGGGGCUCCCAGCCAGGCCCUUGUCGGCCCCACCAGUGCCUCUCCCUGCUGCUCCUAGGACCCGUCUCCAGCUGCUGAGAUCCUGGACUGAGGGGGCCUGGAUGCCCCCUGUGGAUGCUGCUGCCCCUGCACAGCAGGCUGCCAGUGCCUGGGUGGAUGGGCCACCGCCUUGCCCAGCCUGGAUGCCAUCCAAGUUGUAUAUUUUUUUAAUCUCUCGACUGAAUGGACUUUGCACACUUUGGCCCAGGGUGGCCACACCUCUAUCCCGGCUUUGGUGCGGGGUACACAAGAGGGGAUGAGUUGUGUGAAUACCCCAAGACUCCCAUGAGGGAGAUGCCAUGAGCCGCCCAAGGCCUUCCCCUGGCACUGGCAAACAGGGCCUCUGCGGAGCACACUGGCUCACCCAGUCCUGCCCGCCACCGUUAUCGGUGUCAUUCACCUUUCGUGUUUUUUUUAAUUUAUCCUCUGUUGAUUUUUUCUUUUGCUUUAUGGGUUUGGCUUGUUUUUCUUGCAUGGUUUGGAGCUGAUCGCUUCUCCCCCACCCCCUAGGGUACCAGCAGGCAGAGCCUUGCCCUCUGCUCAGGCUGGGGUCCAGUGGGAGGGGCCCAAGAUCUCUGCUCAGAGAAGUGCAGGGGGAGCCUUCCAGCUCACUCUCCCUGAGGACUGGCUUGACAGGGGCUAUGGGUUUGCUUUGGUGUUGUUUUUAAAAAAAGAAAAUAUAUUUUUUUGAAAAAACGACUGCCCAUCCCGGGUCCUUUCCCUGAUGGGUUGGGGCAGUUACCUGGUUGCUGUUUUAAUUAAAAAAAAAAAAAAAAAAAGGACUAAA